ACUCUGCAGUUGAUCCAGCAGCAGGAGGCAGCUGUACCCAUCACUGUCCUCAGAGUACUUUUAAGAACAAGGAGGUCUCUGCCCACGGCAGCCCAAGCAGGAAGCUGGAAUUUGAACCCUGGGACACAGACUUCAGCCACUGCCUUCGCAACAAUUGCUUCUUGAAUGCCCCAAAGCUGGAGAUGAGACGCUGGAAAAGUGCCAUAUGCUCCACAACCUUGCUUGCCAGUAGAGAAGAUCAAGGCAGCAGCCUCUGCCUAAUGUCCACCUUCCAAAUCUCAAGCAAGUACAGCCGAUGCAAGGGCGCUCACUCCUAGCCGGGAUUCUUGUUGUGAGGCACUCUGGGAAAUGUCGUGCUUAGCUUGCAAGCUUGUGAGAUUCCCAUCCAUCAUGACUGCCAUCCGACUACGAGAAUUUAUUGAGCGUCGCCCAGUGAUCCCGCCAAGUAUAUUCAUCGCUCACCAAGGAAGAGACGUUCAAGGCUAUUACCCUGGGCAGCUGGCAAGACUCCAUUUUGAUCAUAGUGCAAAGAGAGCUCCCAGCAAACUACUUCUAUUUCCAUUUAGACCGCUCAUAGACUUGACAAUUCCACCCAAGACAAAAUAUCACUAUCAGCCUCAAUUAGACCAACAAACACUCAUUCGAUAUAUUUGUCUUCGAAGACAUUCAAAGCCUGCCGAGCCAUGGUAUAAAGAAACCACUUACCGACGAGACUAUUCUCUGCCAUUUUAUGAGAUUGAUUGGAACCAGAAAUUAGCCACAGUUUCGCUGAAUCCUCGACCGCUUAAUUCACUGCCAGAGCUCUACUGUUGUGAAGAGAGAAGCAGCUUUGAAAGAAAUGCUUUUAAACUAAAAUAACCACGGCAUUCGAACAAAAUAACGUUUGGCAUUCUUAGGUGGCCCUUUUAGACUAAGUUAAUGGCAGCAGAACUACUUUCAGUUUCAGUGUGUAUACAGAUGGCUAUAAUCCUAAAAUAUUUACAUGUUGCAAAUUCUUUGCAGAUUAAGUUGGUCAGCUUAGAACAGGGAAUCAAGAUCUAUCCUUAAGAGAACUUGAAUUUAAGCCCCACUCCCAGUCUUAUUGCUGAUGCUGGCAAGCUAUCUUACAUUUAGGCCAAUGUAUACGCAGGAUCAGGUAAGAAGAUCAUUGUGUCUGCACAAUAAUUGCAUCGCUGUUGGGAAAAAUAAAAAAAAGAACCGGGGGGACAUGGCCAAUUAUAAAGAAAACUGGCACUGGAGACCCUCAAGGGGCUCUGGAUGGAGAAACCCAGGUGUAGCCUGAGGCUGUAGCGAGAUGUGGGACUGAUAAAAAGGAUUAACUGAGAGUCUGUGUCCAGGAGUUAGCACCCCUAUCUUGGCAAGAAGAAAGCCUGACAACUAGGCAUCAGCUCCUCAGGCAGAAAGCUAAAGGGUCUUCUCUAGGGAGAGGAAAGAAUCCCAAAGGAAAAAAAC